CAUGUUCAAUAGAAACAUAACCGUCCAAUUUAUUUUCUGAAUAUUUUCCAUCUGCUGUUGCUGAAUCUACAGAUGCAGAGCUCCUGGAUACGAGAGCCAAGUGUGCUUUGAGAGUAGGGUGGGUGAGGUUGCUAAUGAGUACAGGGGAGCAGGUGUUGAUCAGGAGGACCCUGCACUGGGGCAUCUGGACGUCCUGCCUCAGGACUUGAGACUCCAGUUGGAUGGCACAGGCAGACUCAGCCCAGGUCAAAGCCGUCCCCUUGAAGUUUCUUUUUAUCCCAAGCUCUUUCUGGCCCCUGGAAUUUGGCAUCCCCUAGGCCCUGUGUGGAAGGACAGAUGAACCAGGUUUUAGAUAACAUGUCUAGAAGAGUGAGCCCCUACUGUGUGCCCGGCACUUUCCCCACAGGAUCCUCUAGCUAGAAUAUCCAAGGGUCAUGGAGAGAAAUACCCAGUUAAAAUAUCAGAAAUGAAAAAGCGAUACCAUUAGAGACACUAAAAAGACCAUUAGGUAAUAGUACUAGCUUUUGUAUUCUGAGAUCCAACAGCAGCAGUCACUUCCCUCCACCGCUAUGUGUAUCCCAGGACCACCCUGGGCAGGGAGGGCUGAGGUUAGGGAGCAGCCAUGGAUGCUCUGAUGCUGGCCCUGGGCCUCGGGGGUGACAGUGAUGAGGAACUGGGUGCACACAUGAGUGGGGCAGCCGGGCCUGGCCAGAGAAGCAGCACACACGUGCACAGAUGUGUUUACCCACAUACACAUGUGCACGCACGUGCACAAACACAUUGCAGGCAGGCAUGUUGACGCCUCAGGCAGCGGAGGACCCUGACUCUGGGCACUGCUGACCCGGGCAAGGCCCCACUGUGAUUCGUGCCAUGACCUCAGAAUGUCACUGGUGCUUAGCACCUAUCUGCUCUCUGGCCUGCGUCAGUGGUCUACAGCAGUUACACACAGGCAGUGGUAUCUGUGAGCAGCUCUGUGGACUCAAAGGUUUUCUCCCUGAGAGGCAUGACCCAGGCCAGCUGAUUCAUCAGAAUCAGGUGAGCGUGACCUGCUCUCUUCCCUCCAGGCGGACUUGGGGGCAGUGGCUACGGUGCGGGCGGUGUUGGCCUCUGUGGGGCAGCUACCGAGGAGGGUCAUCCCUGAGCACUCACCAGGCGCCCGUUCUACACUGCCCGUGUAGACGAUUGGCUCUUUCGUCUCCAUGGUGGCUUCGUAGAGUGGGUGCUGUUCCCAAAUGUCCCCAUUCGACAGAUGAGACGUCUGGGGUCAGAGAGGCAGUAACCGGCCUGGGAAUCCGGACAUGACCCUGAGUUUUGCUCUCAGCCCUGCCGUGUGCUGUGCUGGAAUUCAGGCCUGAACCCUGUGACCUCCCUGCCCUAGAUCCCAAAUCUGCCCAGGUUUCCCAUCCCGAUGGGGCAGAGCCUGGUCCUGGCAGAGCCACUGGUAUAGAGCCACUGGUACAGAUCCACUGACGGUCCUCAGAACACCUCUGUGCCCUAAGCUGGGUCCUGAUGGUCGCUGUGGGCCCCACUGAACACACAUGGUCCCUUGUCCGGGGGAGCCUGCUGCCCUUGGGCAGCUGUGGAAAAUGAAGGAGCCCUGGAGGGCUGGCUGAGGGGAGACUAUCUUCCCUUGUGUUCAAAGGGGUCCGGGCACUAGGGUUCUCCCCAGGUAUUUCUUGCUCUGCGUGGUCCUCUUGAGGCCUCGCCCUCCUUUUGCCUCGAGUAUUCCCAGGAGGGACGGUCCAUCCAGCUGUUCUCCAGGACCAAGGACCCACUGUUCUUCCUCAGUGACCCAGGAAAAUGAAGCCUCCUCCUGUUGGGACGGCUCAGAAUGGUGGACUCCACAGUCCCUCCGCGAGAGACGUGGUUUCCAUGCGUACAAUAGAUCUUCCUCAUCCCCCAAACCCAACACCCUCCUGCUCAACAGGCGUUAUUCCUAAAGUGGCUUCACUGUUCAGACUGAAGAGCCACGGUAGCCAAAGUGAUGAGCGGAGUAGAACCGAGCAGUCGGGAGAGAUCUUGUUCCCUGUAGGAAACUGGGCAUCGCUGAGGCCCUGAGCAUCCCAGGAGGCCGAUUGCACAGAGACCUCUGGUCGCUGACCCCAGUCUGCCUCCACAUCCCUGGAAUAGCCCAUCAUGGGCCCUUCACCCUUGGCAGGUGGAAACCAUUCAACCUGCUGGGGCCGGUGUGUCCCCAUUUCAUGGCAUUGGGGGACAACAGGAUUCUCUGUCUAGGUCCCACUGUACUCAAGUCCUUGGGAAGAUGCCCACCCCUGCUUGGGACUUGAGACUCCAGAGACUGGAGCAGCUGUGGGCCACUGGGUCUGGCCCCUUUUUCCCUGGGGGCGGCGGUGGAAUGGGGGUUACGCAGCCAGCCAGCAUCUGGGAGCCCGGCGAGAGCGGUUCAGGUGUUCUCCGAAGCCGCCGCGUACGGUGUGACCUUUAGACAAUUCUGUCUCACAGGAUGGACGUGGUAGAGGUCGCGGGCAGUUGGUGGGCACAAGAGCGAGAGGACAUCAUUAUGAAAUACGAAAAGGGACACCGAGCUGGGCUGCCAGAGGACAAGGGGCCUAAGCCUUUUCGAAGCUACAACAACAACGUCGAUCAUUUGGGGAUUGUACAGUCCUGCCCCUCCUGGGAGUCAGCCCCACAGGAAGGCCCUUGUCCUCCCUUCCCUGUGCCUUCUCCUGGGCUGAGCCCUGAGCUGGAAAGGGACAGAGCCAGUCCUUUCUGGGGGUCGGCACCCAGGCUGGGGCCGCUCCAGGCCCCGUGCAGUUCCUCAGCUCUGCCUGGGUUGCCUUACAGUGAGACGGAGCUGCCUCCUCUGACUGCGCGGGAGGCGAAGCAAAUUCGGCGGGAGAUCAGCCGAAAGAGCAAGUGGGUGGAUAUGCUGGGAGACUGGGAGAAAUACAAAAGCAGCAGAAAGCUCAUAGAUCGAGCGUACAAGGGAAUGCCCAUGAACAUCCGGGGCCCGAUGUGGUCAGUCCUCCUGAACAUUGAGGAAAUGAAGUUGAAAAACCCCGGAAGAUACCAGAUCAUGAAGGAGAAGGGCAAGAAGUCAUCUGAGCACAUCCAGCGCAUCGACCGGGACGUAAGCGGGACAUUAAGGAAGCAUAUAUUCUUCAGGGAUCGAUACGGAACCAAGCAGCGGGAACUACUCCACAUCCUCCUGGCAUAUGAGGAGUAUAACCCGGAGGUGGGCUACUGCAGGGACCUGAGCCACAUCGCCGCCUUGUUCCUCCUCUAUCUUCCUGAGGAGGAUGCAUUCUGGGCACUGGUGCAGCUGCUGGCCAGUGAGAGGCACUCCCUGCAGGGAUUUCACAGCCCAAAUGGCGGGACCGUCCAGGGGCUCCAAGACCAACAGGAGCAUGUGGUAGCCACGUCACAACCCAAGACCAUGGGGCAUCAGAUCUCUCUCGGGCUCACCCUGCGCCUGUGGGACGUGUAUCUGGUAGAAGGCGAACAGGCGUUGAUGCCGAUAACAAGAAUCGCCUUUAAGGUUCAGCAGAAGCGCCUCACGAAGACGUCCAGGUGUGGCCCGUGGGCACGUUUUUGCAACCGGUUCGUUGAUACCUGGGCCAGGGAUGAGGACACUGUGCUCAAGCAUCUUAGGGCCUCUAUGAAGAAACUAACAAGAAAGAAGGGGGACCUGCCACCCCCAGCCAAACCCGAGCAAGGGUCGUCGGCAUCCAGGCCUGUGCCGGCUUCACGUGGCGGGAAGACCCUCUGCAAGGGGGACAGGCAGGCCCCUCCAGGCCCACCAGCCCGGUUCCCGCGGCCCAUUUGGUCAGCUUCCCCGCCACGGGCACCUCGUUCUUCCACACCCUGUCCUGGUGGGGCUGUCCGGGAAGACACCUACCCUGUGGGCACUCAGGGUGUGCCCAGCCCGGCCCUGGCUCAGGGAGGACCUCAGGGUUCCUGGAGAUUCCUGCAGUGGAACUCCAUGCCCCGCCUCCCAACGGACCUGGACGUAGAGGGCCCUUGGUUCCGCCAUUAUGAUUUCAGGCAGAGCUGCUGGGUCCGUGCCAUAUCCCAGGAGGACCAGCUGGCCCCCUGCUGGCAGGCUGAACACCCUGCGGAGCGGGUGAGAUCGGCUUUCGCUGCACCCAGCACUGAUUCCGACCAGGGCACCCCCUUCAGAGCUAGGGACGAACAGCAGUGUGCUCCCACCUCAGGGCCUUGCCUCUGCGGCCUCCACUUGGAAAGUUCUCAGUUCCCUCCAGGCUUCUAGAAGCAUCUGGGCCAGGGCUCAUGGCUGGAUAAUUUCCCUAGGCUUAACAACCCAAGCAAGCUUCGCAUCCUCGUUUUAUUUUUGGUUAAACUUAUGAAAAUGUAUUAAGAAAGAGUGCAGCUCGAGAGAGAUUCAGAGAUGGAACACACCAGACCCCAGAUCACAAAGCCAACCAUGCCCAGCCCCUCCCAGCACCCCCAGCCCCACGACCAUCGUUCUGAAUUCUGACGACACCGUGAGCCUGCCUUUGUACUUCAAACUCAUGGAAGGAUAACCACCUUCAUGUUUUGAAAUAAAUGUUUCCUGUUGAAAUGA